GGGAUUACAGGCAUGAGCCACCGCGCCCGGCUGCAUGACAUAUAUUUUAGUUUUUGAAAAAUAUUUUAGCAAAAGUCACUUUAGUGAGGCCUUACUUAACUGCACAGUCUAAAAAUAGAACUUCUCCACCACUUCAUUGCUUUUGGUUUUUCCUCACACUCUGUACAUGUGAUUGUGCUGGUCAUCUCCUUCACUAGCAAAUCAGCUCACCAAGUUGGGGCUUUGUCUAUUUACCGUUGUGUUCCCAGUGGACACUCGAUGUUAAGAUUCAACGAAUGAAUGCCUGGACGAGUGGUAUCUGGGCUCACAGGUAACCUCACAGCCCACCGGGAGGACACUGCCAGAGCUGCUCUGCACUGCGAGUCCCGGGCCUUCCCAUUGGACGCUAAGGCACUCGUUAACUGCUGUGUAAACGCAGCCUGACUUCCCUCACCUCAGGCGAGGCCCGCAUCAGGCCCCUCUGACCUAGGACCUCCCGAUCCGGCCGUUAUCGCCAACCGUAUCUGUGUGGUUUCGUGGAGGAAGCGCGGUGGACCUUGAGGGGAGGGUACGCGCAGGCACAAUAAAGCAGAAAGCCGCUAUAAUAAUGAUGAUAAUGAAGAAAAACAAAAGCAUCCAUUCGUCACUUAGUGGCAAGCGUUUUUCCAACUACUUUCCGAGUAGUAACUGCUUGCCAGAGUUUCCCCAGCUUGGGCCGGAAGGUGAGGCGGUAGCUCGAGCUUUGCCUUUCUCAGGCAUUGUCCUGCGUUUGCGGGGCCAGGCGCUGGCACACGGUCACUAACCCCUGGUCGUUAGCUUCGAUUCCCGGCCUGGGAGAGCGCUAUCGGCCACUCCUGGCUGCAUUGCAGUCGCGGCUUUCUCCAGAGCUCCGCCGGGAACGGGAAGCGCUGAAACGUCGCGACCAGUCAGUAGGGUUCCCACGGCCGCAACUCGGGUGUGACGCGGCAGGCUGGCACCAGCGGACACAAGUAUGAGGCUAAGUGAGAAGCGCUCUGCUUCCGAGUGUCAGGAUGGCCGAGUGGUCUAAGGCGCCAGACUCAAGGUUCUUAGACUCUGUGAGUAAAGACAGCUUCAUCUUCCCAGUUCAUCAUGGCUUCAACAUCCAGAGAUGUCAUUGCUGGGAGAGGUAUCCACUCAAAGGUGAAGUCUGCAAAGCUGCUUGAGGUUCUGAAUGCUAUGGAGGAGGAAGAGUCCAACAACAACAGGGAAGAGAUUUUCAUUGCACCUCCCGACAAUGCUGCGGGGGAAUUCACUGAUGAGGACUCAGGGGAUGAAGACAGCCAGCGAGGUGCUCACCUACCUGGCAGUGUGCUGCAUGCUUCAGUCCUGUGUGAGGACUCUGGCACCGGGGAGGAUAAUGACGACCUGGAGCUGCAGCCAGCCAAGAAGAGGCAGAAAGCAGUUGUGAAACCUCAGCGCAUUUGGACCAAAAGAGAUAUUCGUCCAGACUUUGGCAGUUGGACUGCAUCAGAUCCUCAUAUUGAGGAUCUGAAAAGCCAAGAGCUGAGUCCCGUGGGCCUUUUUGAGUUGUUUUUUGAUGAAGGAACAAUUAAUUUCAUUGUUAAUGAAACCAAUCGUUAUGCUUGGCAGAAAAAUGUCAAUUUGAGUCUUACGGCUCAGGAAUUGAAGUGUGUUUUGGGCAUUUUGAUUUUAAGUGGGUACAUCUCUUAUCCAAGGAGAAGGAUGUUCUGGGAAACCUCUCCCGAUUCACAUCAUCAUCUUGUGGCUGAUGCAAUUAGAAGGGACAGAUUUGAACUAAUCUUCUCAUACUUACAUUUUGCAGAUAACAACGAACUUGAUGCAAGUGAUAGGUUUGCCAAGGUCAGACCUCUCAUCAUCCGGAUGAACUGCAAUUUCCAGAAGCAUGCACCCUUGGAAGAGUUCUACAGCUUUGGCGAGUCUAUGUGUGAGUACUUUGGGCACCGGGGGUCCAAGCAGCUGCACAGGGGGAAGCCUGUGCGACUUGGCUACAAGAUUUGGUGUGGGACAACCAGCAGAGGCUACUUGGUGUGGUUUGAGCCCUCACAGGGCACACUGUUUACCAAGCCAGACAGGAGCUUGGAUCUAGGAGGCAGUAUGGUAAUAAAAUUUGUGGAUGCGCUUCAGGAGCGUGGUUUUCUGCCAUAUCACAUAUUUUUUGACAAGGUUUUCACAAGUGUUAAACUGAUGUCCAUUUUGAGGAAAAAGGGGGUGAAAGCCACAGGAACUGUUCGUGAGUACAGGACUGAGCGAUGUCCCCUAAAAGACCCCAAAGAACUGAAAAAAAUGAAGAGGGGUUCAUUUGAUUACAAAGUCGAUGAGAGUGAGGAGAUCAUCGUGUGCCGCUGGCACGAUAGCAGCGUGGUCAACAUUUGCUCCAAUGCUGUGGGCAUAGAGCCAGUGAGGCUGACCAGUCGUCACUCUGGAGCAGCUAAAACGCGGACUCAGGUCCACCAGCCAUCACUGGUGAAGCUGUAUCAGGAGAAGGUGGGUGGCGUUGGUAGGAUGGAUCAGAAUAUUGCCAAGUACAAGGUGAAGAUCCGAGGCAUGAAGUGGUACUCAAGCUUUAUUGGCUAUGUCAUUGAUGCUGCCCUCAACAAUGCAUGGCAGCUGCAUAGAAUCUGCUGCCAAGAUGCCCAGGUGGACCUCCUUGCCUUCCGGAGAUACAUUGCCUGUGUGUAUCUGGAGAGCAAUGCUGACACAACAUCUCAAGGGAGGCGAAGCAGGCGGUUGGAGACUGAGAGCCGCUUCGAUAUGAUUGGGCACUGGAUUAUCCAUCAGGACAAGAGGACCCGGUGUGCCCUCUGCCACUCACAGACCAACACCCGGUGUGAGAAGUGCCAGAAGGGUGUCCAUGCCAAAUGCUUCAGGGAGUACCACAUCCGGUGACAUCAUGAGACAUGCUUCUUUGGUUUAUAAUGAGAUGUUUACAGUUAAAUACAGAUGGCAGUUGAGCACUUCUGUUUUGUGUUGGAAAAAAGACCUGAAUUUCUAAUGACUUGAUUUUCUAUUUUCUCCCUACCCACAAUACAGUUAUCUUUUUUAUUGUGUUGUGUUAUGCCUACAUGUGAUAUAAAUUAAUAUUUAUAUUCAUUUAUAUUUAUAUUUUUGAACUUAUUUAUUUAAAGUUAUGGAUCACUUUUUAUUCAAAUAAAAGUUGUGCUUUGGGGUAUAUUUGAAUCCUAGCAAGAAUAAUCAAAGGAAAACUUGCAAGAACAGUAAGAAGACUUUACCAUUGCAUGCCAUGGUUUAUAAUCUAAGAUAGGCAAUAGUGUAUAAAUAUCAUGUAAAUGUGAUGGAUUUCUUAAUCAUAUUUAUUUCAUAUUAAUCCAAGUUUAUCAAACUUUUGAGGGAUAAUCUGCCUUGUAUUUAGUCAGAGGGCUAGAGGUGCAGAUUUCAUAUUUUCUUAAUGAAAAUAUUUUCCUAAUACACAUAUAUCAAUGUGAGAUUCAUUUUUGUAAAAAAAAUUAUUUUUUUAAUUUUGUGGGUACAUAGUAGGAGUGUAUUUUUAUGGGUUACAUGAGAUAUUCUGAUACAAACAUGCAAUGUAUAAAAAUCACAUCAGGGUAAAUGGGGUAUCCAUCUUGUCAAACACUUGUCCUUUGUGUUUCAAACAAUCCAAUUAUACUGUUAGUUAUUUUAAAAUGUGCAAUUAAAUUAUUUUUAACUAUA